GCUCUGCACCCAGCUCCUUCCCGGGCGCGCACACGCGCUUCCUCUCUUGAGCUCCCGGGCGUCCGGAGGCGAAGGUCCCGGAGCGUUCACGAGAAUCCGGGUCCCGGCGAGUCCGGGGUCCGCUCCUCCAGCUGCGCCCAGGGCGCACGAGCCGGCCAGCCUCGGGGAGAGGGCGCGGGGGCGCUGGGGGUUCUUACGGGAAGAUGAGGAAGCCCGACAGCAAGAUCGUGCUCCUGGGGGACAUGAACGUGGGGAAGACGUCGCUGCUGCAGCGGUAUAUGGAGCGGCGCUUCCCGGACACGGUCAGCACGGUGGGCGGCGCCUUCUACCUGAAGCAGUGGCGCUCCUACAACAUCUCCAUCUGGGACACCGCAGGGCGGGAGCAGUUCCACGGCCUGGGCUCCAUGUACUGCCGGGGGGCGGCCGCCAUCAUCCUCACCUAUGAUGUGAAUCACCGGCAGAGCCUGGUGGAGCUGGAGGACCGGUUCCUGGGCCUGACAGACACAGCCAGCAAAGACUGCCUCUUUGCCAUCGUGGGGAACAAAGUGGACCUCACUGAGGAGGGGGCCUUGGCGGGCCAGGAGAAGGAAGAGUGCAGUCCCAAUAUGGACGCUGGGGACCGUGUCUCCCCAAGGGCACCUAAGCAGGUGCAGCUGGAGGAUGCGGUGGCCCUUUAUAAAAAGAUCCUCAAGUACAAGAUGCUGGAUGAGCAGGAUGUGCCGGCCGCUGAGCAAAUGUGCUUUGAGACCAGCGCCAAGACCGGCUACAAUGUGGACCUCCUGUUUGAGACCCUCUUUGACCUGGUGGUGCCAAUGAUCUUACAGCAGAGAGCUGAGAGGCCGUCACACACAGUGGAUAUAUCCAGUCAUAAGCCACCCAAGAGGACCAGAUCUGGGUGUUGUGCCUGACUUUCGAGGGCCUCCUGGACUCAGACUGUGCAUGUUGGGAAGGGGUCUGACCAGGCAAGCUGUGAUCUGAAAGGAGCAAGGAACAGCAAGGAAUUAUUUUCCAGAAUGACACCCGCAGCAGAAUGUUGGAGUGGAAAUGAUGGCUGGCUAUGAAGAGGAGGUCAACGUGUGUGGUCUCCUCAGUCUCUGUCAGAGGGGUGGGGAGGUGGGAAACAGGAAUCCUCUGCAAAGCCCAAUCUGCAGAGUCGAGACCCCUGGUGCUCUCUGCCCCGCUGCCUGGCACUGGUCCUUUGCAGCCAGCCACCAACGGCCCCCUUGCCCUUGCAGAGGCAGAAGCCUGCGUCUGCACCUGCACCUCUGACCGUUUCAGCACCCUGGGUUGUUACCACGUCCUACAACUCUGACAUUUCUUGUUCUCAAGCGUUUCUCUUCACUGUGAGUUGUCUUUGGUCCUCCCACUUGGUACUUGUAUCUUGAUGCUUUAUAAUCCUGACUCUCGACGUGUUCAUUUAUACAAAAUCAGGAAUAACUUUGUUUUUAUACUGAUUGCAGCAAUGUUGGCUACAUGUAUUAUUAAAGAGGAUUUUUGGAACAACUUA